CCUGGGGACUGUGACUUCCUUGGGAGGAGCUGCCCAUCCUCUUCCCUUUCAUUCUCUCAGCUUUUUGGCCUUUCAGCAAGGAAUUGCUUUAUGUAAACUAAACGUGGAAGAAAAAGAAAUUGUCUUCUCACCUAAUUGUAAAUUAGUGAUGUUUCCCUGGUGCCAGUGAGUAUGUUCAGUUCUUGGAGACUUAAUGUUAGCUUGUCCUUGAACUCUGAGCUGAUGAGUUGUGAUAUCUACCAUUCAAAAGGCCAGGACUGAGUCAUGAUGGGAUUCCUGUGGGGGCAGUUGGCACAUGUCUGGUAGAUUGGGAUAGUGGUGCUGUAGAUGGGUAUUCUCUACUUGUAGUUUUCCGUUUGAGGGUUCCUGGUGCCCUAACUUCGUGGGAUCUGUCCAGCCGCCUUUGUUGAGGUUGGCUUGCCAUAUACAUCCCCUUCUGGAAUUUGAAGAAUGUUUGGUUUCAGACUGCUCCUCCGCACUGACCCGAGACAGGAUAGGAAAUUGGACAGAUAGAACUGACUCGUCCUGCUGUUCUUGUGUACCACGAGUGGAUGAAAUCAGAGGAGCUGCAGCGUUUGACAGCCUCGGAGCCGCUGACCCUGGAGCAGGAGUAUGCCAUGCAGUGCAGCUGGCAGGAAGAUGCAGACAAGUGUACCUUCAUUGUGCUGGAUGCCGAGAAGUGGCAGGCCCAGCCAGGCGCCACCGAAGAGAGCUGCAUGGUGGGAGAUGUGAACCUCUUCCUCACAGAUCUAGAAGACCUCACCUUGGGGGAGAUCGAGGUCAUGAUUGCAGAGCCCAGCUGCAGGGGUAAGGGCCUUGGCACUGAGGCCGUUCUCGCGAUGCUGUCUUACGGAGUGACCACGCUAGGUCUGACCAAGUUUGAGGCUAAAAUUGGGCAAGGAAAUGAACCAAGCAUCCGGAUGUUCCAGAAACUUCACUUUGAGCAGGUGGCUACGAGCAGUGUUUUUCAGGAGGUGACCCUCAGACUGACAGUGAGUGAGUCCGAGCAUCAGUGGCUUCUGGAGCAGACCAGCCACGUGGAAGAGAAGCCUUACAGAGAUGGGUCGGCAGAGCCCUGCUGAUGGCUGGGCCUUGUGGGCAGCCACUCUGUGUGAGCAGGGUGUUGGGCCCAUACACUUCAAAGACCAGAGCCCUGCACUGGGAGAGUGCUCCUGGCCCAGGCUGGGAAUCACCUUUCGAGGCCCUUCAGACUCUGGCGGGGCUUGCUGUGGCCUCCCUCCAGCUAGUGGUGUGGCUGAGCAGACUCCAGGGCCAGGGCCAGUUCCCUUCUCCCCUCCCGGCCAAACCCAGACCCAGACUCUAGGAAGCUGGAAUGGAGGGCAGGGAUCCAUGGGAGAUGUCGGGAUGAAGGUGGGAGCUGGAGGUGCAGGGGGACCUGGAACAUGGAUGGGAGUGGACAGGCCUUUCUCCUUAGAGGCCAGAGGUGCUGCCCUGGCUGGGAGUGAAGCUCCAGGCACUACCAGCUUUCCUGAUUUUCCCGUUUGGUCCAUGUGAAGAGCUACCACGAGCCCCAGCCUCACAGUGUCCACUCAAGGGCAGCUUGGUCCUCUUGUCCUGCAGAGGCAGGCUGGUGUGACCCUGGGAACUUGACCCGGGAACAACAGGUGGUCCAGAGUGAGUGUGGCCUGGCCCCUCAACCUAGUGUCCGUCCUCCUCUCUCCUGGAGCCAGUCUUGAGUUUAAAGGCAUUAGUGUUAGAUACAGCUCCUUGUGGCUGGAAAACACCCCUCUGCUGAUAAAGCUCAGGGGGCACUGAGGAAGCAGAGGCCCCUUGGGGGUGCCCUCCUGAAGAGAGCGUCAGGCCAUCAGCUCUGUCCCUCUGGUGCUCCCACGUCUGUUCCUCACCCUCCAUCUCUGGGAGCAGCUGCACCUGACUGGCCACGCGGGGGCAGUGGAGGCACAGGCUCAGGGUGGCCGGGCUACCUGGCACCCUAUGGCUUACAAAGUAGAGUUGGCCCAGUUUCCUUCCACCUGAGGGGAGCACUCUGACUCCUAACAGUCUUCCUUGCCCUGCCAUCAUCUGGGGUGGCUGGCUGUCAAGAAAGGCCGGGCAUGCUUUCUAAACACAGCCACAGGAGGCUUGUAGGGCAUCUUCCAGGUGGGGAAACAGUCUUAGAUAAGUAAGGUGACUUGCCUAAGGCCUCCCAGCACCCUUGAUCUUGGAGUCUCACAGCAGACUGCAUGUGAACAACUGGAACCGAAAACAUGCCUCAGUAUAAAACAAACAUUAUAAAACGAACGCGUUGCUUGCCGUGGC